AGCAGUGACAGCUACUUCCCGGAUGAGAAGGGCGGCCGUGAAGCCAGCAGGGAAGCCAGCCCCACAGCCAAGGGCCCCCCAGCCUCCUCACAGCUCCCCAUAGCCUGGACCUGCCGGCCCUCCCUCCAGGACCGAGGGGCUCCCAAGGGAAACUCAGGCGUGUGCUGGUCCCAAUGUCAGUGAAACCCAGCUGGGGGCCUGGCCCCUCGGAGGGGGUCACCGCAGUGCCUACCAGUGACCUUGGAGAGAUCCACAACUGGACCGAGCUGCUUGACCUCUUCAACCACACUUUGUCUGAGUGCCACGUGGAGCUCAGCCAGAGCACCAAGCGCGUGGUCCUCUUUGCCCUCUACCUGGCCAUGUUUGUGGUUGGGCUGGUGGAGAACCUCCUGGUGAUAUGCGUCAACUGGCGCGGCUCAGGCCGGGCAGGGCUGAUGAACCUCUACAUCCUCAACAUGGCCAUCGCGGACCUGGGCAUUGUCCUGUCUCUGCCCGUGUGGAUGCUGGAGGUCACGCUGGACUACACCUGGCUCUGGGGCAGCUUCUCCUGCCGCUUCACUCACUACUUCUACUUUGUCAACAUGUAUAGCAGCAUCUUCUUCCUGGUGUGCCUCAGUGUCGACCGCUAUGUCACCCUCACCAGCGCCUCCCCCUCCUGGCAGCGUUACCAGCACCGAGUGCGGCGGGCCAUGUGUGCAGGCAUCUGGGUCCUCUCGGCCAUCAUCCCGCUGCCUGAGGUGGUCCACAUCCAGCUGGUGGAGGGCCCUGAGCCCAUGUGCCUCUUCAUGGCACCUUUUGAAACGUACAGCACCUGGGCCCUGGCGGUGGCCCUGUCCACCACCAUCCUGGGCUUCCUGCUGCCCUUCCCUCUCAUCACAGUCUUCAAUGUGCUGACAGCCUGCCGGCUGCGGCAGCCAGGACAACCCAAGAGCCGGCGCCACUGCCUGCUGCUGUGCGCCUACGUGGCCGUCUUUGUCAUGUGCUGGCUGCCCUAUCAUGUGACCCUGCUGCUGCUCACACUGCAUGGGACCCACAUCUCCCUCCACUGCCACCUGGUCCACCUGCUCUACUUCUUCUAUGAUGUCAUUGACUGCUUCUCCAUGCUGCACUGUGUCAUCAACCCCAUCCUUUACAACUUUCUCAGCCCACACUUCCGGGGCCGGCUCCUGAAUGCUGUAGUCCAUUACCUUCCUAAGGACCAGACCAAGGCGGGCACAUGCGCCUCCUCUUCCUCCUGUUCCACCCAGCAUUCCAUCAUCAUCACCAAGGGUGAUAGCCAGCCUGCUGCAGCAGCCCCCCACCCUGAGCCAAGCCUGAGCUUUCAGGCACACCAUUUGCUUCCAAAUACUUCCCCCAUCUCUCCCACUCAGCCUCUUACACCCAGCUGAGGUAGAGGCCAGACUCCUCCAACAGUGAAGGAAAAGGCACAGGUGAGAGUAUAGGUGGGAGAUUUGGGGGGAUGUAGAGGGGAGGGUCAAAGCACUCGUGGUCAAUUUUGAAUCUAUCUUAAAAUACUGAGGUGUGGAGAGAGAGACAGGAUCAGGAGCGAUAGAGAGCAGGCCCUCAGUGUUGUACUAUUUGUCUCGGUCCUUGUGUCUAAGGAGCAAUGCAGAAAAAAAGGUGAAAUAAAUGGAAGAGAUAGCCAUGGACUCUGGAUCUUUUAAAAAUCUGCACUUCCAGCUGGGAUUGGGAAGGGAGCUGAGGCUAAAGAGGUGCUCGGCAGAGGAAACUAGACACAUUCAUUUCAUAAAUCACUCUGGCUGGAAACAGUGAACUCUGCAGGAACCUCACAAAACUCCUUUUGCGUUUGUGAGCUUGUUGAUCUUCCAGCUCACUAUGCAGGUUAUGGGGACAAGAGGCCAGAGGCCAAGGAACCAGGCGGCCCCAGCAGGACGUUCCCUAGCUGUGCAUCCUAUGCACAGCCAUGAUAAGUGAAGGCGGAUGGGGAUGGCAGGGGUGGGGGCGAAGCCAAGGUCUGAGACCUGCACCCUGCAGCUGGGUCAGCAGGAUGGUAUCUCCACCCGCGGCCAUCCAGGAAACACAGCUCCAUUUCCUUGCUGACACCCUCCCCUCCCCGUUGUCCAUCCUGCUCCCUCCCCACAAGCAAGAGGAGUUGUCCCAGAGUCAGCUCCUCAUAGCUGACCUCUUACCAGCUUCGGAUCUAGGAAACUUCCAGACUUCUAGGGAGACACAGAGCUACCAGAAAGCCCAACCCACCCCCAUCUCUUUCUCUCCAGAUCAUAGGAAAGUAUCAAGGGAUGUCAUUCCGGGAGCAGCCCUUGGGACAGCCAGCAGCAGGUGCUGGCAGAUGCUCUGUCCUUCACCCUCUGUCCCCGGCACCAGAUGGGGAAGGCCACAGUGGAAACUUCUCAAUUCCGUCACAGGGCAGAGCUCUGACACUGUUAUAAGUCAGUUCUCCCUGGCCAUGUCUUUUCCUAAUUUUCCUGUCCCACAACUUAGGUUCCUUAACACUUGUUCUACAGAUGAAACAAAAAAGUCCUCUGUUAACAAGUAGACCUUCUGGAAAAGGAUCACUUAUGUUUGGGAGACUAGGACCCUGUCCAUGAAGAACUCUGAAGUAAAGGCCUAAGAACAGGAUCUAGUUUCCGCCUUCCAAUUCCACGUCCUUUGCCUCUUAAUCCUGCCCGUGGUAAGGGGACUGGAUGGAAUCACUGAUAGCCUCUUCACCAUCUCCUCUGUCCUGCUUAAGUGCUCCAUGUGUCUGGAAUGUUUAACUUGGAGUAACUACUCACUGACUUGGAGACCACCUGUUCUACUUUGAGAAAUCAGAACUGUUCUGUGGAUGCACUGACAGCGUGCUCCAACUGCAUAUGCACCCAGGUUUGUCAGGAGCAUGGAAGGAAACCUGCAUCUCCCUGUUUACUGGGCCCAAACCUGAAAGGGUCUUAAGCUGCAGACAGCUUCUCAGUAGCACAGAGCUGAAGGCUUUUUGAACCAGGAGUCUGGGUUGUGGCUUGGGUCGCAGUAAGGGCUUAGCCUAUCAAUGCAGAAUUCACAUUGAAAAAGACUUUCCUCUCUUGUCCCAACACAAAAAAGCAAGCCAAGAUCUGAUGCCCAUAUCACUGCCUCCUCUGACUUGGGCUACAGGAGUUUCCUGAAGGAAACCAAAUUUUACAUCUCUGUCACAUUCCAGAUCACCUUAGAGGCCACGCUCCCAAGAUUAGUUAUCACCCUGGCAGUAUGAAUACUUCCCUAAGGCCUCCCAUCCAUGGAGGGGAAGAGUGGGAACCAGCUGUUACACUCAGCAUCUACUGAGCACUGAUGGGAGCCCUGCCUGGGCCAUGUGCUGUGGGGCCAAAUGGACAUCACUCCCUAACUUCUUGAGGUCUGUCUCCUCUGUGGAUUCACGCAUGUAUCAACCUCAUUAAACUAUGCCAAACUUUUGCCUCC